AGCAGAAAAGUCCAAAGCAGUGUGAGGACAACCGCCAGGUGGUGGCUCAGAGGAGGACACAGUCGCUGUGGGCAGGUGGUCAGGGCGCAGGAGGGAAUGAGCUGUGGAUUUUUAGUAAUCUACAACAAUCAGGCAGUUCCAGGACACAGGGAAGUGAGUGUGAACAGCCAAUGGACCCGGAGCCGAGAGCCUGGGCAGGCGUAGGCUGGACUAUGGACGCCCUGCAACCCUGCCAGGCUGGGAAGGGGAGGCUUGAUCCUGAGCGCGUGUUAGGAAGGAGAUGCCCAGGUUCAGGUGUAUCGUGCAUUUUUUUUCCACAGUGCAGAAAUGACAUUUCUGGUUGGUCUUGAAUGUCUGCUCUGGCCAAGCCACCUCCUCUCAUGCUAGCUAACCAAGUGGCACGUGUGCCCACGCAGGCCAUUCUAAGGAACACUGUAAUUGUCUAGACAAUUUUCUCUCAAAUACUCCGUCCUGGAAGCGUCUGGUUGGCAGAAGAGGGAAGGCAGGAGGGUGGCAGCGUCCCGGCUGAGUCCUCUUGCACAUGGGAGCUGGAGUCCAGCCAGGCUCCAGAGCGGCUCCGGCUGGCAAGGGACCUGAACAGGAAGAUGAGACUCGAGGUUUUCUGCAUGUGAGUUUGGGGUGAAGCUGUGGAUGUGGGGUGGGCGGGCUGGGGUUGACAGUCAUCUGUUUUGGAAGCCCUUAGGCCCUGCCGGUUAGAUGUGCAUGCAGCCAGGGGUCCGAGCGUUCUCCAGAGGAAGGGACCGUGCUGGCCCCUACAGGAAAGGAAGCUGCAGGCUGGUCUGGGUGGCCUCCAGAGGACCCCACGCAGCUGGCAUGAGGGCAGCCAGGCUCCUAAUGAGCCAGGAACGACAAUAAUCCAGUUCCUGAGUGUUUGGGCAGAACUCUUUUCAUCGCUUACCAGGCCUGUUUGGGAGGAAGGACUGAAUCUGUUCAGUGUUUUGAGGCCACAGCUCAGCUCGGGGAGCUCAGCGCCACUGCCCCCUUCUGUCUGCUGGGACUCCCUCGUUUUUCUGCAAAGAGGGCCAGGCAGACUGUUCCGAGUUUCCAGACUUGGGAACAUUCUCCUGCUCCCUAAAUACACCCCUGCCCUCCAACACAGACACAUAUUGGCAUGGCAGGAGAGGGGGGGAAGUGAUAGAUCUCUCUCAAUGAGGGUAAAAAAUGGUGCUGAAGAGGAGAAAUGCCAUGCAAUUUGAGACGUGAGUUAAUCCUUCAGUUACCUGGGGCCCCACAUCCCCAACAGCUGCCACGGCUUCCCAGGAUGGGCAGGAGGGACCCAGGCAAAAUAGAAAAGGAACCAGGAUUAGUGUCCUGAGACCGUCCCCAAACCUUGGAGUGCUGUCCUCACUGGCUUUAACUGGGUGCUGGCUUUAAUUCCCGCAGUGUUCAAAGCCAAACAUCUCUUGAUCACUGGGUUUCAUUUUUGAAGUCUUGGGAAACCAGAGGACAGUUCAUCAUCGUGUGCUUCCAGGGGCUGGGCCCAGGUCUGCUGUGAAAAGAUGCUGUCAUCUGAGCUCAGCGUUCAUGCCCGUGUCUCUCAGUCACUCACUGGAGUUGGGGACGGGCUUAUCUGUUAGGAUGAUAAAACUUCCAUAGCAUACGCCUUGCAUUUGCUGGUAUCUGUCCCAAAGGGCUUGUCAGUUUUUACAUAUAUUAUCUCAGCAUCUUCUAGAUGUCUCUGCAGAGGAGCUAUUCCUAUGUAGACAGUCAUUCCUGUGUAGACAGUGAGUAAUAGGCUGAGCAGCUUGCCCAAGAUUAGUCAGAAUUGAAGCCAGCGCCAGCCCCCAUCCUUAUCUGGCUCCAAUCUGAUUUGCAUAUCUCAAGCUUACUGUGUUUUAUUUACCCAUCUGUAUAAAGGGUUCAAUGCUUCUUAAGACAUCUACAGAAAAAUCUAUAAAAAGGAAGACACGUAGAUUCUUCCUUUGGUGCUAUGAAAAUGUCACUAUUAAAUAUUUCCUGUUUUCCAGUUAGUUUUUAGUUUUUAGGUAAAGAUCAAUAAAAUGGAAUAUGUCCAUUAUUGUUUUUAAAAAAAUCAUUCUGUUGCCUAUAUAUCAGAAAAGAUCUUUCAUUACGCAGAGUAAGAAGUCUAAAAGUCUGUUUUCAAGGCUAGUGCCAAUGUGUUUUUAAAACGCAGGUGGCCAGCCUUGCCAGUUCAGGAAUGAUUCUUGGCGUUUUCAAACUCAAACGUUCCUCCUUCCAGCUAAUCUGUGGAUUCUUCACUCGCACCAUUUGCAGGACAAGUGGCUGCCAGGGCCAGGGACUUUUCACCGGGUGACCAACAGCAACAUAGUGUGGGGAAUUUUCUACUCUGGGCCAUUUGCUGAGAGGGCUCCUGGGCCUAAGCUGCUACCACCUCCUUUAUCUCUCCCUGUCGGGUGACUCUAUAAAAAGACAGGAGAAGCUGAGGCUCAUUCACUCACUUUGUCCACUUCAUUCCCAAGAGAAGUGUCGGGGGGACCUGCCAGGCUUAGGGGAAGCUCUGAGCUGAGCCCCUUGUGCAAAGAGGCGAGCCACCCAGAGGCAGCUGUUCCCUUCUAGGCCUGGAAGUGCACAUGCUCAUCUACAGCUUUCUUGGAAGAAGAAAGAAACAAAAACUGAGAUUUAGAACACCAGGUCUGUUUCCACUGGCGGCCACUCUUGGGCACUGGAGACCAGCAAGAGCUUUGUUUUUAAAAGGCUCUUCCAUGGCAGAUAUUCGCAGAGGCAUCAGGGCUACACUUAAAUGAAGGGCUCCGGCUGGCACCUGAGGAGCGGCGUGACCCCGAGGGCCCAGGGAGCUGCCCGGCUGGCCUAGGCAGGCAGCCGCACCAUGGCCAGCACGGCCGUGCAGCUUCUGGGCUUCCUGCUCAGCUUCCUGGGCAUGGUGGGCACGUUGAUCACCACCAUCCUGCCGCACUGGCGGAGGACAGCGCACGUGGGCACCAACAUCCUCACGGCCGUGUCCUACCUGAAAGGGCUCUGGAUGGAGUGUGUGUGGCACAGCACAGGCAUCUACCAGUGCCAGAUCUACCGAUCCCUGCUGGCGCUGCCCCAAGACCUCCAGGCUGCCCGCGCCCUCAUGGUCAUCUCCUGCCUGCUCUCGGGCAUAGCCUGCGCCUGCGCCGUCAUCGGGAUGAAGUGCACGCGCUGCGCCAAGGGCACACCCGCCAAGACCACCUUUGCCAUCCUCGGCGGCACCCUCUUCAUCCUGGCCGGCCUCCUGUGCAUGGUGGCCGUCUCCUGGACCACCAACGACGUGGUGCAGAACUUCUACAACCCGCUGCUGCCCAGCGGCAUGAAGUUUGAGAUUGGCCAGGCCCUGUACCUGGGCUUCAUCUCCUCGUCCCUCUCGCUCAUUGGUGGCACCCUGCUUUGCCUGUCCUGCCAGGACGAGGCACCCUACAGGCCCUACCAGGCCCCGCCCAGGGCCACCACGACCACUGCAAACACCGCACCUGCCUACCAGCCACCAGCUGCCUACAAAGACAAUCGGGCCCCCUCAGUGACCUCGGCCACGCACAGCGGGUACAGGCUGAACGACUACGUGUGAGUCCCCACAGCCUGCUUCUCCCCUGGGCUGCUGUGGGCUGGGUCCCCGGCGGGACUGUCAAUGGAGGCAGGGGUUCCAGCACAAAGUUUACUUCUGGGCAAUUUUUGUAUCCAAGGAAAUAAUGUGAAUGCGAGGAAAUGUCUUUAGAGCACAGGGACAGAGGGGGAAAUAAGAGGAGGAGAAAGCUCUCUAUACCAAAGACUGAAAAAAAAAAUCCUGUCUGUUUUUGUAUUUAUUAUAUAUAUUUAUGUGGGUGAUUUGAUAACAAGUUUAAUAUAAAGUGACUUGGGAGUUUGGUCAGUGGGGUUGGUUUGUGAUCCAGGAAUAAACCUUGCGGAUGUGGCUGUUUAUGAAA